GCAGAAGCCUGAAGACCAAGGAGUGGAAAGUUCUCCGGCAGCCCUGAGAUCUCAAGAGUGACAUUUGUGAGACCAGCUAAUUUGAUUAAAAUUCUCUUGGAAUCAGCUUUGCUAGUAUCAUACCUGUGCCAGAUUUCAUCAUGGGAAACAGCUGUUACAACAUAGUAGCCACUCUGUUGCUGGUCCUCAACUUUGAGAGGACAAGAUCAUUGCAGGAUCCUUGUAGUAACUGCCCAGCUGGUACAUUCUGUGAUAAUAACAGGAAUCAGAUUUGCAGUCCCUGUCCUCCAAAUAGUUUCUCCAGCGCAGGUGGACAAAGGACCUGUGACAUAUGCAGGCAGUGUAAAGGUGUUUUCAGGACCAGGAAGGAGUGUUCCUCCACCAGCAAUGCAGAGUGUGACUGCACUCCAGGGUUUCACUGCCUGGGGGCAGGAUGCAGCAUGUGUGAACAGGAUUGUAAACAAGGUCAAGAACUGACAAAAAAAGGUUGUAAAGACUGUUGCUUUGGGACAUUUAACGAUCAGAAACGUGGCAUCUGUCGACCCUGGACAAACUGUUCUUUGGAUGGAAAGUCUGUGCUUGUGAAUGGGACGAAGGAGAGGGACGUGGUCUGUGGACCAUCUCCAGCCGACCUCUCUCCGGGAGCAUCCUCUGUGACCCCGCCUGCCCCUGCGAGAGAGCCAGGACACUCUCCGCAGAUCAUCUCCUUCUUUCUUGCGCUGACGUCGACUGCGUUGCUCUUCCUGCUGUUCUUCCUCACGCUCCGUUUCUCUGUUGUUAAACGGGGCAGAAAGAAACUCCUGUAUAUAUUCAAACAACCAUUUAUGAGACCAGUACAAACUACUCAAGAGGAAGAUGGCUGUAGCUGCCGAUUUCCAGAAGAAGAAGAAGGAGGAUGUGAACUGUGAAAUGGAAGUCAAUAGGGCUGUUGGGACUUUCUUGAAAAGAAGCAAGGAAAUAUGAGUCAUCCGCUAUCACAGCUUUCAAAAGCAAGAACACCAUCCUACAUAAUACCCAGGAUUCCCCCAACACACGUUCUUUUCUAAAUGCCAAUGAGUUGGCCUUUAAAAAUGCACCACUUUUUUUUUUUUUUUGACAGGGUCUCACUCUGUCACCCAGGCUGGAGUGCAGUGGCACCACCAUGGCUCUCUGCAGCCUUGACCUCUGGGAGCUCAAGUGAUCCUCCUGCCUCAGUCUCCUGAGUAGCUGGAACUACAAGGAAGGGCCACCACACCUGACUAACUUUUUUGUUUUUUGUUUGGUAAAGAUGGCAUUUCACCAUGUUGUACAGGCUGGUCUCAAACUCCUAGGUUCACUUUGGCCUCCCAAAGUGCUGGGAUUACAGACAUGAACUGCCAGGCCCGGCCAAAAUAAUGCACCACUUUUAACAGAACAGACAGAUGAGGACAGAGCUGGUGAUAAAAAAAAAAAAAAAAAAGCAUUUUCUAGAUACCACUUAACAGGUUUGAGCUAGUUUUUUUGAAAUCCAAAGAAAAUUAUAGUUUAAAUUCAAUUACAUAGUCCAGUGGUCCAACUAUAAUUAUAAUCAAAAUCAAUGCAGGUUUGUUUUUUGGUGCUAAUAUGACAUAUGACAAUAAGCCACGAGGUGCAGUAAGUACCCGACUAAAGUUUCCGUGGGUUCUGUCAUGUAACACGACAUGCUCCACCGUCAGGGGGGAGUAUGAGCAGAGUGCCUGAGUUUAGGGUCAAGGACAAAAAACCUCAGGCCUGGAGGAAGUUUUGGAAAGAGUUCAAGUGUCUGUAUAUCCUAUGGUCUUCUCCAUCCUCACACCUUCUGCCUUUGUCCUGCUCCCUUUUAAGCCAGGUUACAUUCUAAAAAUUCUUAACUUUUAACAUAAUAUUUUAUACCAAAGCCAAUAAAUGAACUGCAUAUGAUAGGUAUGAAGUACAGUGAGAAAAUUAACACCUGUGAGCUCAUUGUCCUACCACAGCACUAGAGUGGGGGCCGCCAAACUCCCAUGGCCAAACCUGGUGCACCAUUUGCCUUUGUUUGUCUGUUGGUUUGCUUGAGACAGUCUUGCUCUGUUGCCCAGGCUGGAAUGGAGUGGCUAUUCACAGGCACAAUCAUAGCACACUUUAGCCUUAAACUCCUGGGCUCAAGUGAUCCACCCGCCUCAGUCUCCCAAGUAGCUGGGAUUACAGGUGCAAACCUGGCAUGCCUGCCAUUGUUUGGCUUAUGAUCUAAGGAUAGCUUUUUAAAUUUUAUUCAUUUUAUUUUUUUUUGAGACAGUGUCUCACUCUGUCUCCCAGGCUGGAGUACAGUGGUACAAUCUUGGAUCACCGCCUCCCAGUUUCAAGUGAUCUCCCUGCCUCAGCCUCCUAAGUAGCUGGGACUACAGGUAUGUGCCACCACGCCUGGCUAAUUUUUAUAUUUUUAGUAGAGACGGGGUUUCACCAUGUUGUCCAGGCUGGUCUCAAACUCCUGACCUCAGGUGAUCUGCCCACCUCUGCCUCCCAAAGUGCUGGGAUUACAGGCAUGAGCCACCAUGCCUGGCCAUUUCUUACACUUUUGUAUGACAUGCCUAUUGCAAGCUUGCGUGCCUCUGUCCCAUGUUAUUUUACUCUGGGAUUUAGGUGGAGGGAGCAGCUUCUAUUUGGAACAUUGGCCAUCGCAUGGCAAAUGGGUAUCUGUCACUUCUGCUCCUAUUUAGUUGGUUCUACUAUAACCUUUAGAGCAAAUCCUGCAGCCAAGCCAGGCAUCAAUAGGGCAGAAAAGUAUAUUCUGUAAAUAGGGGUGAGGAGAAGAUAUUUCUGAACAAUAGUCUACUGCAGUACCAAAUUGCUUUUCAAAGUGGCUGUUCUAAUGUACUCCCGUCAGUCAUAUAAGUGUCAUGUAAGUAUCCCAUUGAUCCACAUCCUUGCUACCCUCUGGUACUAUCAGGUGCCCUUAAUUUUGCCAAGCCAGUGGGUAUAGAAUGAGAUCUCACUGUGGUCUUAGUUUGCAUUUGCUUGGUUACUGAUGAGCACCUUGUCAAAUAUUUAUAUACCAUUUGUGUUUAUUUUUUUAAAUAAAAUGCUUGCUCAUGCUUUUUUGCCCAUUUGCAAAAAAACUUGGGGCCGGGUGCAGUGGCUCAUGCCUGUAGUCCCAGCUCUUUGGGAGGCCAAGGUGGGCAGAUCGCUUGAGCCCAGGAGUUCGAGACCAGCCUUGGCAACAUGGCGAAACCCUGUCUUUACAAAAAAUACAAAAAUUAGCCGGGUGUGGUGGUGUGCACCUGAAGUCCCAGCUACUCAGUAGGUUCGCUUUGAGCCUGGGAGGCAGAGGUUGCAGUGAGCUGGGACCGCAUCACUACACUUCAGCCUGGGCAACAGAGAAAAACCUUUUCUCAGAAACAAACAAACCCAAAUGUGGUUGUUUGUCCUGAUUCCUAAAAGGUCUUUAUGUAUUCUAGAUAAUAAUCUUUGGUCAGUUAUAUGUGUUAAAAAAUAUCUUCUUUGUGGCCAGGCACGGUAGCUCACACCUGUAAUCCCAGCACUUUGCGGGGCUGAGGUGGGUGGAUCAUCUGAGGUCAAGAGUUCAAGAUCAGCCUGGCCAACACAGUGAAACCCCAUCUCUACUAAACAUGUACAAAACUUAGCUGGGUAUGGUGGCGGGUGCCUGUAACCCCAGCUGCUCCAGAGGCUGUGGCAGAAGAAUCGCUUGAACCCAGGAGGCAGAGGUUGCAGCGAGCCAAGAUUGUGCCAUUGCACUCCAGACUGGGUGACAAGAGUGAAAUUCUGCCUAUCUAUCUAUCUAUCUAUCUAUAUCUAUAUAUAUAUAUAUAUAUAUCCUUUGUAAUUUAUUUUUCCCUUUUUAAAAUUUUUUAUAAAAUUCUUUUUUAUUUUUAUUUUUAGCAGAGGUGAGGUUUCUGAGGUUUCAUUAUGUUGCCCAGGCUGGUCUUGAACUCCUGAGCUCAAGUGAUCCUCCCACCUCAGCCUUCCAAAGUGCUGGAAUUGCAGACAUGAGCCACCGCGCCCCUCCUGUUUUUCUCUAAUUAAUGGUGUCUUUCUUUGUCUUUCUGGUAAUAAGCAAAAAGUUCUUCAUUUGAUUUGGUUAAAUUUAUAACUGUUUUCUCAUAUGGUUAACAUUUUUUCUUGCCUGGCUAAAGAAAUCCUUUUCUGCCCAAUACUAUAAAGAGGUUUGCCCACAUUUUAUUCCAAAAGUUUUAAGUUUUGUCUUUCAUCUUGAAGUCUAAUGUAUCAGGAACUGGCUUUUGUGCCUGUUGGGAGGUAGUGAUCCAAUUCCAUGUCUUGCAUGUAGGUAACCACUGGUCCCUGCGCCAUGUAUUCAAUACGUCGUCUUUCUCCUGCGGGUCUGCAAUCUCACCUACCAUCCAUCAAGUUUCCAUAGGGCCAUGGGUCUGCUUCUGGGCUCCCUGUUCUGUUCCAUUGUCAAUUUGUCUAUCCUGUGCCAGUAUCACACUGUGUUUAUUACAAUAGCUUUGUAACAGCUCUCGAUAUCCGGUAGGACAUCUCCCUCCACCUUCUUUUUCUACUUCAGAAGUGUCUUAGCUAGGUCAGGCACGGUGGCUCACGCCUGUAAUCCCAGCACUUUGGGAGGCCGACGCGGAUGGAUCACCUGAGGUCAGGAGUUUUGAGACAGCCUGGCCAACAUGGUGAAACCCCAUCUCUACUAAAAAAUACAAAAAUUAGUCAGGCAUGGUGGCAUGUGCCUGUAAUCCCAGCUAUUUGGGAGGCUGAGGCCGGAGAAUUGCUUGAACCCGGGGGGCGGAGGUUGCAGUGAGCCGAGAUCGUACCAUUGCACUCCAGCCUGGGUGACAGAGCGAAACUCUGUCUCAGGAAAAAAAAGAAAAGAGAUGUCUUGGUUAUUCUUGGUUCUUUAUUAUUCAAUAUAAAUUUUAGAAGCUGAAUUUGAAAAGAUUUGGAUUGGAAUUUCAUUAAAUCUACAGGUCAAUUUAGGGAGAGUUGAUAAUUUUACAGAAUUGAGUCAUCUGGUGUUCCAAUAAGAAUAAGAGAACAAUUAUUGGCUGUACAAUUCUUGCCAAAUAGUAGGCAAAGCAAAGCUUAGGAAGUAUACUGGUGCCAUUUCAGGAACAAAGCUAGGUGCGAAUAUUUUUGUCUUUCUGAAUCAUGAUGCUGUAAGUUCUAAAGUGAUUUCUCCUCUUGGCUUUGGACACAUGGUGUUUAAUUACCUACUGCUGACUAUCCACAAACAGAAAGAGACUGGUCAUGCCCCACAGGGUUGGGGUAUCCAAGAUAAUGGAGCGAGGCUCUCAUGUGUCCUAGGUUACACACCGAAAAUCCACAGUUUAUUCUGUGAAGAAAGGAGGCUAUGUUUAUGAUACAGACUGUGAUAUUUUUAUCAUAGCCUAUUCUGGUAUCAUGUGCAAAAGCUAUAAAUGAAAAACACAGGAACUUGGCAUGUGAGUCAUUGCUCCCCCUAAAUGACAAUUAAUAAGGAAGGAACAUUGAGACAGAAUAAAAUGAUCCCCUUCUGGGUUUAAUUUAGAAAGUUCCAUAAUUAGGUUUAAUAGAAAUAAAUGUAAAUUUCUAUGAUUAAAAAUAAAUUAGCACAUUUAGGGAUACACAAAUUAUAAAUCAUUUUCUAAAUGCUAAAAACAAGCUCAGGUUUUUUUCAGAAGAAAGUUUUAAUUUUUUUUCUUUAGUGGAAGAUAUCACUCUGACGGAAAGUUUUGAUGUGAGGGGCGGAUGACUAUAAAGUGGGCAUCUUCCCCCACAGGAAGAUGUUUCCAUCUGUGGGUGAGAGGUGCCCACCGCAGCUAGGGCAGGUUACAUGUGCCCUGUGUGUGGUAGGACUUGGAGAGUGAUCUUUAUCAACGUUUUUAUUUAAAAGACUAUCUAAUAAAACACAAAACUAUGAUGUUCACAGGAAAAAAAGAAUAAGAAAAAAAGA